AGGCUCUAUUUAGAGCCGGGUAGGGGAGCGCAGCGGCCAGAUACCUCAGCGCUACCUGGCGGAACUGGAUUUCUCUCCCGCCUGCCGGCCUGCCUGCCACAGCCGGACUCCGCCACUCCGGUAGGAUUCCCCGCCUGUCAUUCCCUAGCCCAGCUCUUGGGAAACUGCAGAGGGGUCCAGAGGAUUUGCAGUUCUGAACCUGCACACUCCAGUCUAGGAUCUCCGAGCAAGAGCGUAGCCUCAUGGCUGCAACCUGUGAGAUUAGCAACAUUUUUAGCAACUACUUCAGUGCGAUGUACAGCUCGGAGGACUCCACCCUGGCCUCUGUUCCCCCUGCUGCCACCUUUGGGGCCGAUGACUUGGUACUGACCCUGAGCAACCCCCAGAUGUCAUUGGAGGGUACAGAGAAGGCCAGCUGGUUGGGGGAACAGCCCCAGUUCUGGUCGAAGACGCAGGUUCUGGACUGGAUCAGCUACCAAGUGGAGAAGAACAAGUACGACGCAAGCGCCAUUGACUUCUCACGAUGUGACAUGGAUGGCGCCACCCUCUGCAAUUGUGCCCUUGAGGAGCUGCGUCUGGUCUUUGGGCCUCUGGGGGACCAACUCCAUGCCCAGCUGCGAGACCUCACUUCCAGCUCUUCUGAUGAGCUCAGUUGGAUCAUUGAGCUGCUGGAGAAGGAUGGCAUGGCCUUCCAGGAGGCCCUAGACCCAGGGCCCUUUGACCAGGGCAGCCCCUUUGCCCAGGAGCUGCUGGACGACGGUCAGCAAGCCAGCCCCUACCACCCCGGCAGCUGUGGCGCAGGAGCCCCCUCCCCUGGCAGCUCUGACGUCUCCACCGCAGGGACUGGUGCUUCUCGGAGCUCCCACUCCUCAGACUCCGGUGGAAGUGACGUGGACCUGGAUCCCACUGAUGGCAAGCUCUUCCCCAGCGAUGGUUUUCGUGACUGCAAGAAGGGGGAUCCCAAGCACGGGAAGCGGAAACGAGGCCGGCCCCGAAAGCUGAGCAAAGAGUACUGGGACUGUCUCGAGGGCAAGAAGAGCAAGCACGCGCCCAGAGGCACCCACCUGUGGGAGUUCAUCCGGGACAUCCUCAUCCACCCGGAGCUCAACGAGGGCCUCAUGAAGUGGGAGAAUCGGCAUGAAGGCGUCUUCAAGUUCCUGCGCUCCGAGGCUGUGGCCCAACUAUGGGGCCAAAAGAAAAAGAACAGCAACAUGACCUACGAGAAGCUGAGCCGGGCCAUGAGGUACUACUACAAACGGGAGAUCCUGGAACGGGUGGAUGGCCGGCGACUCGUCUACAAGUUUGGCAAAAACUCAAGCGGCUGGAAGGAGGAAGAGGUUCUCCAGAGUCGGAACUGAGGGUUGGAACUAUACCCGGGACCAAACUCACGGACCACUCGAGGCCUGCAAACCUUCCUGGGAGGACAGGCAGGCCAGAUGGCCCCUCCACUGGGGAAUGCUCCCAGCUGUGCUGUGGAGAGAAGCUGAUGUUUUGGUGUAUUGUCAGCCAUCGUCCUGGGACUCGGAGACUAUGGCCUCGCCUCCCCACCCUCCUCUUGGAAUUACAAGCCCUGGGGUUUGAAGCUGACUUUAUAGCUGCAAGUGUAUCUCCUUUUAUCUGGUGCCUCCUCAAACCCAGUCUCAGACACUAAAUGCAGACAACACCUUCCUCCUGCAGACACCUGGACUGAGCCAAGGAGGCCUGGGGAGGCCCUAGGGGAGCACCGUGAUGGAGAGGACAGAGCAGGGGCUCCAGCACCUUCUUUCUGGACUGGCGUUCACCUCCCUGCUCAGUGCUUGGGCUCCACGGGCAGGGGUCAGAGCACUCCCUAAUUUAUGUGCUAUAUAAAUAUGUCAGAUGUACAUAGAGAUCUAUUUUUUCUAAAACAUUCCCCUCCCCACUCCUCUCCCACAGAGUGCUGGACUGUUCCAGGCCCUCCAGUGGGCUGAUGCUGGGACCCUUAGGAUGGGGCUCCCAGCUCCUUUCUCCUGUGAAUGGAGGCAGAGACCUCCAAUAAAGUGCCUUCUGGGCUUUUUCUAACCUUUGUCUUAGCUACCUGUGUACUGAAAUUUGGGCCUUUGGAUCGAAUAUGGUCAAGAGGUUGGAGGGGAGGAAAAUGAAGGUCUACCAGGCUGAGGGUGAGGGCAAAGGCUGACGAAGAGGGGAGUUACAGAUUUCCUGUAGCAGGUGUGGGCUUACAGACACAUGGACUGGGCUGGGAGGCGAGCAAAGGAAGCAGCUGAGACUGUUGGAGAACGCUUACAAGACUUCAUGCAAGCAAGGACAUGAACUCAGAACACUGAGGUCAGAAGCAUCCUGCUGUCAUGACACCGCUCGAGUGACCUUGACCUUGACCAAGUCUGUCCUGUUUAGGACUGAUUUUUCCUAUUAGGCUAGGGUUUGGACCUGAUGUUCUCAAGAUGUCUAGAAUUGCAUGGCUGGCCUUGUGGAAUAGAUGGUUUUGCAUUCCAGCCAAGUGUGCUGUAAACUGUAUAUCUGUAAUAUGAAUCCCAGCUUUUGAGUCUGACAAAAUCAGAGUUAGGAUCUUGUAAAGGAAAAAAAAAAAAAAACAAAACAAAAUGGAGAUGAGUACUUGCUGAGAAAGAAUGAGGGAAGGAGUUGGCAUUUGUUGAAAGUGUAGUCUUUUUCUCUUUUUUUUUUAAUUGCAACUUUUACUUUAGAUUUAGGAGGUCGUGCGCAGGUUUGUUACAUGGGUAUAUUGUGUGAUGCUGAGCUUGGGAUGCGAAUGAUCCUGUCACCCAGGUAGUGAGUAUAGCACCCAGUGAAACUGUAGUCUCAUGCCAGGCACUGUGCUAGCCCACUCUGGCUCAUUUAAUCCUCUCCUAAGAAGAGAGGAGACACAGCGUCCCCAUUUGACAGAUGCAGAAAGAGGUUCCACAGGUGUGCCUUGAUUCUGUCCUAAAACCGUUUCCCGGAAGCUUUUCCUGGUGUGGGCGCUUCUAACCUAAUCCUCAAUCGAUUCCAGAACUAUUACUCUGUUUCCACAGUGAUACUGUGUCUAGGUUUUAGGGAGGACAGUUCAUUGAUGUUACUUAAGAAUGCUUUCCAGGUGGAAAGUUCCUUAAGUUUGAGGCUUCAAAUUCCAUACAGCACAUUAAAAUCCCAUUCAUGAGUUUGAAAUACUGCUCUGUUGUCUUGGAAAUACCAAUCAGAUUGUUGGCUGAAGUGAUGUGGAUAAAGAAGGGAUCUUAGAAAAA